UAUCGCUACACUGCCGCGGCGAGUACCGGGUUGGCGGCGCUAUCCUGGGCUACACCGCCGGUGGCGGGAGGCGUUUUAGGGGCGCUAUCUGGUGCUGCACUGCCCGCGCAGGAGUUGGGUUGGGUGACCUACUCCAGGCGUCACUGCCCGAGGCUGGGGGCUGAUUUGGGGCGCUAUCCCGGGAGUCAUUUCCUGUGGCGAGGGGCUGGUUGAGGGUGGUAUCCGUGGCUGCACUGCCCACAGCACAGAGCGGGUUUGGGGAGUUAUCCCGGGCUGCGCUGCCCGUGGCAGGGGGCAGGCUGCCAGCGCCAUUGGGUGCUGCAUGUACUAGGCACGGAUGAGUUAGGGGCGCCAUCUGGGACUGCACUGCCGGUGGCGGGCGGUGGAGGUGUCAGUGACAGCGGUGGUCUGCAAGAGAGGAGCGGUCCUCCUCUUCCCGGCCACCUCCUCCUGUUCUUGCUCAAGUGCGGCGGGCGCACAGCAUUUCCUGAGCGCGGCAGGGGCCCCAGCCCCGUGGUGCUUCCUGGACCCGCCUCCUAUUGCUCUGUGUUGCAGAGACCGCCUGGGACCCCGGGGCACGCAGUAGUGGACACGAGGAGGCUACAGGGCCCUGUGGGUGGAGGAGGCAUCAGGAACGGGAACCGGCACUUGGGUGGGGAGGGCUGGCUGGGGUUGAGUUUCUGCUGCUCCUGCUUCCCGAGGAGUGCAGCCAGGGUGGCUGCAGCUGUUCCUGUGGAGUGGGAAGCCCGGGCACUGUGGUGUCUGCAGUCCCCACUCCAGGCCGCAGUUCCUGGCCAGCUUGCGCUAAAAGGAGAGGCUGGACUUUGAAGUGUGGGUGCUUUUCUGGCUUUGUCUGCCCGGAUGCCCAGUGCCCUGAGAAGGAGCUACAUGCCACGGGCUGGAGGCUAGAGCCUGUGGCACCAUGAUUUGCCUCCGAUGGAGGUGGCUGAAUUAGGCUUCCCAGAGACUGCAGUGUCCCAAUCCAGGAUCUGUCUAUGUGCUGUAUUGUGUGGCCACUGGGACUUUGCAGACAUGAUGGUGAUAAGGAGCCUGAGAUUCAUCACUUCUCUGGGUCAAGACCUGAGUCUCAGCCUGGAGGACAUUAUGUUAAGCAAAAUAAAUCAGGACCAGAAAGAUAAAUACCGCAUGUUCUCACUCCUAUAUGGGAGCCUCAUCAGGUUAGAGGGUGUGGAAGGGCGUGACCCAGUGGGAGGUGGGAAUCUCACCAAUAAAAGGCCCUCGUGUGCCCCUUCCCCACAAGACCUGAGCGCCCAGUGGAAGCAGCUGGAGGACAGAGGAGCUUCCAGCAGAAGAGUGGACAUGGCUGCACUCUUCCAAGAAGCAAGCAGCUGUCCCGUCUGCUCAGACUAUCUGGAAAAACCAAUGUCCCUGGAGUGUGGAUGCGCCGUCUGCCUCAAGUGCAUUAAUUCACUGCAGAAGGAGCCCCAUGGGGAGGAUCUACUUUGCUGUUGCUCUUCCAUGGUCUCUCGGAAGAACAAAAUCAGGCGCAAUCGGCAGCUAGAGAGGCUGGCUUCCCACAUCAAGGAACUGGAGCCCAAGCUGAAGAAGAUUCUGCAGAUGAACCCAAGGAUGCGGAAGUUCCAAGUGGAUAUGACCUUGGAUGCCAACACAGCCAACAACUUCCUCCUCAUUUCUGACGACCUCAGGAGCGUCCGAAGUGGGCGCAUCAGACAGAAUCGGCAAGACCUUGCCGAGAGAUUUGACGUGUCCGUUUGCAUCCUGGGCUCCCCUCGCUUUACCUGUGGCCGCCACUGCUGGGAGGUGGACGUGGGAACAAGCACAGAAUGGGACCUGGGAGUCUGCAGAGAAUCUGUUCACCGCAAAGGGAGGAUCCAGCUGACCACAGAGCUUGGAUUCUGGACUGUGAGUUUGAGGGAUGGAGGCCGCCUCUCUGCCACCACGGUGCCGCUGACUUUCCUCUUCGUAGACCGCAAGUUACAGCGAGUGGGGAUUUUUCUGGAUAUGGGCAUGCAGAACGUUUCCUUUUUUGAUGCUGAAAGUGGUUCCCAUGUCUAUACAUUCAGGAGCGUAUCUGCUGAGGAGCCAUUGCGCCCAUUUUUGGCUCCUUCAGUUCCACCUAAUGGUGAUCAAGGUGUCUUGAGCAUCUGUCCUUUGAUGAACUCAGGCACUACUGAUGCUCCAGUCCGUCCUGGGGAGGCCAAAUAAGCCCUCACUCCAAAAAAACAAAAAACAGGGUAAGAAAAUUACUUGGGUGGGUAGACUUAGGAACGCUCUACUUCGUAAAAGCAUUAUACAAAGUCACGGGAGAAAAAUAUGGGACAUUUCUUGAUUGUACUUAAUCUAAUUUGAUUAGAUUAUAGAGUCCUAAGUAUUAAUUAUUGCCACCAUCAAACUCAUUGAGUCCUAUGGUUCACAUCUUGUUUCCUAUAGAAAUGUCCUGUAUUCUGGGAUCAAUUUCCAAAUGCUUUACUUUUUUAUUUCUGCAAGUUCAAAUUAAUGUAUUAUAGAAGUUAUGAGUUAAAUAAAGAUUGGAAUAUCA